AGACCUACCCGGGCGAAGCGGGCGAGCGGUGGUUUGGACGCCGGCGGAGACGCGGGCGAGUGGUUAGCAGGAAGAAGAUGAGCCUUAAGUCUGAACGCCGAGGAAUUCAUGUGGAUCAAUCGGAUCUCCUGUGCAAGAAAGGAUGUGGUUACUACGGCAACCCUGCCUGGCAGGGUUUCUGCUCCAAGUGCUGGAGGGAAGAGUACCACAAAGCCAGGCAGAAGCAGAUUCAGGAGGACUGGGAGCUGGCGGAGCGACUCCAGCGGGAGGAAGAAGAGGCCUUUGCCAGCAGUCAGAGCAGCCAAGGGGCCCAAUCCCUCACAUUCUCCAAGUUUGAAGAAAAGAAAACCAACGAGAAGACCCGCAAGGUUACCACAGUGAAGAAAUUCUUCAGUGCAUCUUCCAGGGUCGGAUCAAAGAAGGAAAUUCAGGAAGCAAAAGCUCCCAGUCCUUCCAUAAACCGGCAAACCAGCAUUGAAACGGAUAGAGUGUCUAAGGAGUUCAUAGAAUUUCUCAAGACCUUCCACAAGACAGGCCAAGAAAUCUAUAAACAGACCAAGCUGUUUUUGGAAGGAAUGCAUUACAAAAGGGAUCUAAGCAUUGAAGAACAGUCAGAGUGUGCUCAGGAUUUCUACCACAAUGUGGCCGAAAGGAUGCAAACUCGUGGGAAAGUGCCUCCAGAAAGAGUCGAGAAGAUAAUGGAUCAGAUUGAAAAGUACAUCAUGACUCGUCUCUAUAAAUAUGUAUUCUGUCCAGAAACUACUGAUGAUGAGAAGAAAGAUCUUGCCAUUCAAAAGAGAAUCAGAGCCCUGCGCUGGGUUACGCCUCAGAUGCUGUGUGUCCCUGUUAAUGAAGACAUCCCAGAAGUGUCUGAUAUGGUGGUGAAGGCGAUCACAGAUAUCAUUGAAAUGGAUUCCAAGCGUGUGCCUCGAGACAAGCUGGCCUGCAUCACCAAGUGCAGCAAGCACAUCUUCAAUGCCAUCAAGAUCACCAAGAAUGAGCCGGCGUCAGCGGAUGACUUCCUCCCCACCCUCAUCUACAUUGUUUUGAAGGGCAACCCCCCACGCCUUCAGUCUAAUAUCCAGUAUAUCACGCGCUUCUGCAAUCCAAGCCGACUGAUGACUGGAGAGGAUGGCUACUAUUUCACCAAUCUGAGAUGGUUUCUACCCCGACUGUUUCCCAGGCUGGUCUGAACUCCUGGUCUCAAGCAAUCCUCCCACCUCGGCCUCCCAAAGUGCUAGGAUUACAAGCACGAGCCAACACGCCUGGCUCAGAUGUCUGUUGAAUUGGGCAUUUGCAGUGCCAUGUCUGUACUAAUAAUUGCUACCGUGUAUUCAUUGCUCGCUGCAGGCCUCUCGGAAGCACGUGACAUGUUAUGUUGUUUAAUUCUCACAAUAAAUCUAGGUGGUAUUUCCCCCCAUUUACAGGUACAGAAACCUCAGAGAGCUUAAGUAACUUUCCCACGGUCACUCACUGUUGUUGUUAAGUGAAAGAGGUGACAGUGAACUCAGGUUCAGUCACUUCAGAGUUGUUCCUUUUUUUUUUUUUUCCUGAGACAGUCUUGCUCUGUCACCCAGGCUGGAGUGCAGUGGCGUGAUCUUGGCUCACUGCAACCUCCGCCUCCCAGGUUCAAGCAAUUCUCCUGCCUCAGUCUCCCAGGUAGCGGGGAUUACAGGCGCCCACAACUGCGCCCAGCUAAUUUUUGUAUUUUUAGUAGAGAUGGGGUUUCACCAUGUUGGCCAGGCUGGUCUCAAACUCCUGACCUCAUGAUCCACACGUCCCAGCCUCCCAAAGUGCUGGGAUUACAGGCUUGAGGCACCGGGCCCGGUCUGGAGCUGUUCUUUUAACCACUUGAUGUUAAAAUAUUCAUUUGAGGAUCAGAGGUCUGUGUGCCACACCUACUUGGGGACUAUAUCCUGGGUGGGGAUAGCAGGUCUGGGAAGACUCAGACAGAAUGGCUUCAUGGUGCACCUGGGGAGGCUGCACCCAGACAUCGGCCCUGGAGCUCCUGGGAGUGUAUAGGAAGCACGACCGGGGAUAGGAGUAGGUAAUUUUUGAGGCUGAAAUACACAGAAGUUCAUGAGUUUGUUUUGUUUACUUUAGCUUCUGUUUUAAAUGGUCUGUGAUCAAAAGAUUUUUACAAAUCGACUCGAGUAUGCAUAGCUUUCCUAAUAUGACUGUAUUAACGUCCUCUUCUUGUAGUGCUGUGCUGUGGCUUUCAUUGAGAAGCUAGACGCCCAGUCUUUGAAUCUAAGUCAGGAGGAUUUUGAUCGCUACAUGUCUGGCCAGACCUCUCCCAGGAAGCAAGAAGCUGAGAGUUGGUCUCCUGAUGCUUGCUUAGGCGUCAAGCAAAUGUAUAAGAACUUGGAUCUCUUGUCUCAGUUGAAUGAACGACAAGAAAGGAUCAUGAAUGAAGCCAAGAAACUGGAAAAAGACCUCAUAGAUUGGACAGAUGGAAUUGCAAGAGAAGUUCAAGACAUCGUUGAGAAAUACCCACUGGAAAUUAAGCCUCCGAAUCAACCGUUAGCAGCUAUUGACUCUGAAAACGUUGAAAAUGAUAAACUUCCUCCACCACUGCAACCUCAAGUUUAUGCAGGAUGAUCACAAUUUAGUGGAGAGUAUUUAUUUGAGCCUAAAUUGUAGGUAGCCCUUACUACACUCAACUGAUUGGGAUCUAGAAUGUAACUAAAUUGCUUAUAAAUGUCAGCAUUUUUUAAAGGUACAGUAUAUGGGGAUUGUUUCGUUUUUCCUAGCAGGGGAACCUUAGUUAAUAAUAAAAUACUACUUAUUUGAGUUACUGAUACAGAUUCAUUUAAGGCUUGUGUGCAAAUUUUGUCUCAAUCUUUUUUCCCUCCAUGAUUUUCCUAUGUGCUUCCUCUGGCAUUCACUGUGGUUUUGGUAAAUAAUUGCCUUUUAAAGGAUUAAACAAAUGAAUGCUACAAAGUGUAUGUUCAAGAAAAUUAAAUGGUACCACUCUUCCACAGUUUGGAAUAAUUUUAUAAUUGUAAAGAUAGAAAUUAUAUUGAUAAGUAAAUAUGUAAAAUUGUAAAUAUGUAAAAAAAAGAAUGGUGUCUGCUGUGCAUGGCAUUUUAUAUGUUAAUUUUUUAGUUUAAAAUGAAGUAUAUUGAAUGUUUGCCUUUAGCACCAUUUUAUUUGGUUUGUCCCACUAAAAUGACUCGAGAAGUGUUUAGACAAACUCCCCUUAAGAUGUGCACUCCAUCUUUAAGAACGUGUUAGCCUUAACUUUGAGGUUCUAUAUAGUCAGAGACUAUGACACCACUAAGGUUCAGAAUAAAGUUUAGGCCACAUAAAAUUGCUGUUUAAUGUAGUCGAUGGAAGACUUUAAACUAUGCUUCUAGCUUAUUUUUCCCUCAUUCAUUCAGCAAAUCUCUAUUGAGUUCUUCAGUGAGAAGGAGCAGGCACUGGGCCUGGAAUGGAAGGCGGGAAUGAAUGGGCCUCUGAUGGUGAGAGGUGACGGGGUCCCUCAGCUGUGAGAUGCAAGGGGCGCCUUGCAGCCUCCAUAAUAUACAUUUGACUUUGCAAACGUCUAGACAUGUUUUCUGAACCUUUUUCAGGACAUUUCAACCUCGGGACUAUUCAUAUUAGUGGCCUGAGAGGUGUUUGUUGUGGGGCCACCCUGUGCAUGGUAGAAUGUUCAGCAGCAUUCCUGCCAUCCAUAUCCAUUAGGUGCCAGUAGCACCCCCGCUAGAGCUGUGAAAAAUUCUCUCCAGACAUAGUCAGAUGUCUCCUGGGGCCAUAUCACCCCUCCGUUAAGAACCACUGAUGUCUUUUACAAACCAGGAGUUAUCCUCCUGGUGGUUAAUAUGGUGUAACCAAAGAAUCUUGCACUCAAUGCACAGUGUGAUGUUAACUAAAACGAGUUAAAUAUUUAGGAGGCUUGACAGCUACCUGCAUUGUAGAACCUUUUCUUAUCUCAGUGGAACCUUCUAUAACCUAAAUAUACCAUUGAUGAUUCUUCUUCCAUUCAGUGACAUCCACAGAUUAUGCAGCUAUACUUGUGAAAUCGUGCAUGAGGCCCCAGGGCACCGUUCUAGAACAACGUCACUUCACACAGGCAGCUGAGAAAGGUUCUCUUGCUUUUCCAGUAUCUUCCUAAGGAUGGAGCCCAAAAUUGCAGAGCAGUAACUUUGGAAUAAAACCAGGGUGGGUAUAAAACUUCUUAUUCUUAAAUUUACAUAUAAGAUCUAUUAAGCUUGACACAUCUGUGUCAUCACGCACUGAAGACAGGAAGCAGUUCACUGAGUCAGCUGGUUCCCAAGCUCGCACAGAAGGUGAUAAGUUACUAUCAAAUGCCAGUGAGAAUCUUCUUAUAGAAUAACCUGGGCCCAAGUGAUUUUAGUACAAAACUUGCCCUUCUUUGGUUUAAUUUUCUAUGUGCUUUUAGGUGUGAAUCCAGAUAUGCGGUCUUAAUUCCUUUGGAAAUACACAGUUCGUUUAGUUACUGUACACUCUGUUUGUUCAAUAAACUGCAUAUCAACUUCCCACAAAAGCUGACUUUUUUGGGUCUCUUACAUAUAAAGUAGGUUAUUGAGUUGAUUUUUUUGGAGGUAUCUCAUAUUGGUCGAAUUCUUCUGGUAUGGACUCUUGCCUUAUAUAGAGGCUUCUAUUUCUCUUAAGUCAGCAUCAAUACAACGGCCGGAGUUUCUGUUUUUGCAAUAAGAAGAUGUUGGUAUUUUAUGUAGGGUAAAUGUGACUGGAAUACACCUUUGGAACGGAAUUCUUUAUCAAUAAAGUUUCACAAUCCGUCCCUCUUCCAAAAA